AGACGCGAGGAGGGAGGCGGCUGAGCAGCGCGGGCGGCUCUGCGGCGGGCGCGGUGGGCGCGGGCGGCGGGGCCCCGGGAUCCCCGCGCGCCUCCUCCGCGCGGCGCCGCCGCCGCGCGUCCCCACGCCCCGCGCUCCACGGCGCCCUCGCCCCGCGCGCCUCUCGUGCCCGCCUCCUGCCAGUCUCCGGGCCGCGGCCGUCUGCAGAGCGAGCGCUCAGACGGAGCCCCCGGGCAACUUGAGUGGCGCCGAUCGGCGGCGGAGCCUCUGGCAGAGCCCCCCGACCCGGCAGCGCGGAGGGGACUCGCGUCCGUCCGCGUCGCGUCACCCCAAACCCUAAGCAGCGCCGCCCCAUCGGCGCGGAGCUCCGGCUGGAGGCAAGAGCCGCGCGCCGGGAGACACGCACCGUGAGCGGCAGCGCCGCCGGCCUCCCUCCUCGCCGCCCCGGAGGGCGAAGCCGCGGCUCCCCAGCCCUUUGCUGCGCCGCGACAGCGCCGGAACACGCCCCGCCUCGCUGCCGCCUUCGCUGUGCCGCCGGCGGAGGGGGCCGCGAGCCCCGCGCCCCGGCCGGAGGAUGUGCGCCCCCGCGGGCCGCCCAGCCUGAGCCAUGCGCCCCAACGGCGGCGGCGCGCCGGCCGGCAUGGAGCCCCGCGCGGCCGCGCUCUGACUCGCUGUGCGCCCCGCGGCCGGCGGGCGGCGGGAGGCGGCGGACCGAGAGCCGGAGACCGGCGCCGCGGGACGGAAGCGAGCGGGCGCGGGCGCCGCGCAGAUGGCCUGGGCGAGCCAGGUCUGAGGCCCCGCUCCCCGAAACGUGACCAUGUGGAUUCAACAGCUUUUAGGACUCAGCUCCAUGUCCAUCCGCUGGCCGGGCCGCCCCCUCGGAAGCCAUGCCUGGAUACUGAUAGCCAUGUUUCAGCUCGCCGUGGACCUGCCCGCCUGUGAGGCCCUGGGCCCGGGGCCGGAGUUCUGGCUCCUGCCGCGGUCGCCGCCCCGGCCGCCCCGGCUGUGGAGUUUUAGGAGUGGACAGCCAGCGCGGGUCCCGGCCCCGGUGUGGAGCCCCCGGCCGCCCCGAGUGGAGCGGAUCCACGGGCAGAUGCAGAUGCCUCGAGCCAGACGGGCCCACAGGCCCCGGGACCAGGCGGCCGCCCUCGUGCCCAAGGCAGGACUGGCCAAGCCCCCAGCUGCUGCCAAAUCCAGCCCUUCCCUCGCCUCUUCGUCCUCGUCCUCGUCCUCCGCGGUGGCCGGUGGGGCCCCGGAGCAGCAGGCCCUCCUGAGGAGGGGCAAGAGGCACCUGCAGGGGGACGGUCUCAGCAGCUUCGACUCCAGAGGCAGCCGGCCCACCACAGAGACUGAGUUCAUCGCCUGGGGGCCCACGGGGGACGAGGAGGCCCUGGAGUCCAACACAUUUCCGGGCGUUUACGGCCCCACCACGGUCUCCAUCCUACAAACACGGAAGACAACUGUGGCCGCCACCACCACCACCACCACCACGGCCACCCCCAUGACGCUGCAGACUAAGGGGUUCACCGAGUCCUUGGAUCCCCGGAGAAGGAUCCCAGGUGGGGUUAGCACAACGGAGCCUUCCACCAGUCCCAGCAACAACGGGGAAGUCACCCAGCCCCCAAGGAUUCUGGGGGAGGCCUCAGGUCUGGCUGUCCAUCAGAUCAUCACCAUCACCGUCUCCCUCAUCAUGGUCAUAGCUGCUCUCAUCACAACUCUUGUCUUAAAAAAUUGCUGUGCCCAAAGCGGGAACACUCGUCGGAACAGCCACCAGCGGAAGACCAACCAGCAGGAGGAGAGCUGCCAGAACCUCACGGACUUCCCCUCGGCCCGGGUGCCCAGCAGCCUGGACAUAUUCACGGCCUAUAACGAGACCCUGCAGUGUUCUCACGAGUGCGUCAGGGCAUCUGUGCCCGUGUACACCGAUGAGACGCUGCACUCGACGACGGGGGAGUACAAAUCCACAUUUAAUGGAAACCGACCCUCCUCUUCUGAUCGGCAUCUUAUUCCUGUGGCCUUCGUGUCUGAGAAAUGGUUUGAAAUCUCCUGCUGACUGGCCGAAGUCUUUUUUACCUCCUGGGGGCAGGGCAGACGCCGUGUGUCUGUUUCACGGCGGUUGUCCGGAAUGCCAGUGGCUCCUGGGCAGAUGUGCACCCCAGAUUCAGCCUUUGUGAUAGAUUCCAACACGUUCUGGCCUCAGACCACCUUUGUGGUGGGGCCAGACUGCUCUGGGCAAAGUGAAGCUGGCCUUUAUGCUCCAAGGAAGGGGGCCUCGAGAGCAGGCCUGCAUUGGCUCUCGGACUAAUUCGCGAUCAUCUUUCAUACAGCAGGAUUCCGUUGGUGAACCUGUAAAAACAAAACAAACAAAACAAAACAAAAAAGACAAAACCUAAAACUGAGCUAUCUAAGGGGGAGGGUCCCCGCACCUACCACUUCUGUUUGCCGGUGGGAAACUCACAGAGCAGGACGCUCUAGGCCAAAUCUAUUUUUGUAAAAAUGCUCAUGCCUAUGGGUGACUGCCUUCUCCCAGAGUUUUCUUUGGAGAACAGAAAGAAGAAAGGAAAGAAAGGAACCAGAGGCAGAGAGACGAGGAUACCCAGCGAAAGGGACGGGAGGAAGCAUCCGAAACCUAGGAUUCGUCCUACGAUUCUGAACCUGUGCCAAUAAUACCAUUAUGUGCCAUGUACUGACCCGAAAGGCUCGGCCGCAGAGCCGGGGCCCAGCGAAUCACGCAGAGAAAUCUUACAGAAAACAGGGGUGGGAAUCUCUUCCGAUAGAGUCGCUAUUUCUGGUUAAUAUACAUAUAUAAAUAUAUAAAUACAAACACACACACACACUUUUUUUGUACUGUAGCAAUUUUUGAAGAUCUUAAAUGUUCCUUUUUAAAAAAAAGAAUUGUGUUAUAGGUUACAAAAUCUGAUUUAUUUAACAUGCUUAGUAUGAGCAGAAUAAACCAGUGUUUUCUACUUUGGCAACUCACGUCACACACAUAUUACACACAUGUGCGCAUUACACACACACAAUACACAUACAUGCAUAUAGACGCAUCUAUUGGAAAUGCAGUUCCACAGGUGAGCAUGUUCUUUCUGGUGACCUGGUAUUCCAUCACCAUUCACCCCAGGGGACAGCCUCGACCGAGACAAGGAGGCCCUUAAAUGACAGCCUGCAUUUGCUAGACGGUUGGUGAGUGGCAUCAAAUGUGUGACUUACUAUCUUGGGCCAGAACUAAGAAUGCCAAGGUUUUAUAUAUGUGUGUGUAUAUAUAUAUAUAUAUAUAUAUAUAUAUAUAUAUAUAUGUUUGUGUGUGUAUAUAUAUAUAUAUAUAUAUAUGUUUGUGUGUGUAUAUAUAUGUUUGUGUAUAUAUAUACACAUAUGCAUACAUAUGAUUUUUUUUUUUCAUUUAAGUGUUGGAAGAUGCUACCUAACAGCCACGUUCACAUUUACGUAGCUGGUUGCUUACAAACGGGCCUGAGCCCCUGGUUGGGUGGGUGGUGGAUUCUUGGACGUGUGUGUCAUACAAGCAUAGACUGGAUUAAAGAAGUUUUCCAGUUCCAAAAAUUAAAGGAAUAUAUCCUUAUGAUGUGUGUGUGUAAUAUCAGGGCAGAACUUAGACAUACGUGAAGGGCCCCGGUUGGUUUGAAAACGAAAAAUAGUCAUUCUGUGUGCAAACCACAAGGCUGCCCCAGUCAGGCAGCGCCCUGACCUGGCCUGUGCUGCAUUGCCUUCCCUUGCGCAGGUGGGCAGGUGUGGCCCGCUUUUUCUAGGGCCCAAGGGUGACUUGGAAUCUUGGGGGAAGCCUCGGCAAAGAUGCCGUUCUCCCGUCAGCUUCCAUUGGCCGAUGGAUGUUUCUGUUUUGUCACCGAGAAUCCUACUAUAAACUACCCAGUGGAAACAGGGGCCCCAGACCUGAGCCUCAGUACAGAGAAUCCCAACCACACACACUUUAUUAAAAAUACUGCCAUGCCGCCGGGCCUCCCUCACAAGCCUCACCUGAAACGGGCUCACUGGUGCCCCAGACUUGCUGUCAACAGCGGGUGCUGUAGGGAUCUAGGGAUGCAUCUCAUGGCCCACGCUGUGCCUCCUUAAAGGAUGUUUCCUGUCCAUGGGAGACGCCUAACAUGGUGUGGGUCCCUGUCUCCAAAGACUAUAUUUCUCACGCGUGGCCCACGUGCAGCUUUAAUUUCAGCAGUAGAGUGCAUGAGCCAAUUCAGUGAAAUGUCACAGGCCAGGCAAAAAGGUUAAAGAUCAGACAGACAGCUGACCUUACUGCCCUCAAUGGCCAGGCUGAUGACCUGAUUCUUCCCUUGGGCUCAGUCUCCCUCUAAAACACCUUGUGAUAUGCUUCAGAAGUUCACUUUUGUAUCUCCUGAAACAUGUGAACCUAGAGUAAGGCCUCCGGAGGUGAAAGGAUUGUUUUUGUGAUGCAGCAGUGUUGAGAUCUGUAUCCAUGGUAUUGCUCACAAAUUAGGAAAAGUUGUUCUUUAGUUUUUGUUCUGUCAUUUAUUUUCCCCCCAAGCUUUGGCACAUCCUGAGACAAUGCAAACAUCCGCCACUGGCAUUUGGCCGUCUCCAGGUUCCUGGCACUCACCUGCAUGGCGCUCCAGCCUGCAGCUCUCUCUGCGCGCCAUCCGGCCUCGUCCAUCCCAUUCUCCUUCAAUCACUCCCUCCCGCUGAGGUGGGCCUCCUGACUCCAGGUGAGCACAGCGUGGUGCGAGUGCAUGGUGAGGGCUGGCGGCGGCCAACAGGCAGUGGGGUGGCUGCUCUGGUCUCUGACAUUCUGAGCUCCAGAGUGAGCCCAACUAAGGAGGAGGUGACGGCCGGGGGGCCCUGUUGGUUCGCUGAUCAUGAGAACCUAGGAUUCCCGAGGGACUCCUGGUAUCUGCUCUGUCAACUCCCAGCUGCUCAGCCCCCUUCUCUGACCAUGUGCGGCACCCUGGAUGCCCUGAACUCUUUCCUGGGUCCAUAAGACAUCGAGCCUUGGAAGGAAGCGUAAUGCAACAACCCUCUUGUCCCCGAUAAGAGCCACAGAUUCAAGGCAGGGCUGUGAGACCCACACAGGCACAAACACCAGACAAGCAAGUGCAUGCCCAUUCCACACCCAAAAGUCUGGUUCUGUACCAACAUGACAUCCGUCAAGGUAAAUCCACACAAAGGCUGCUAUUUCUGGAUGAUUGAGGCAGUGUCUGUAGACGUGUUACUUUACUUUUUUAAAUGGUUACCUGCUCUCCCAGACCCCUCACCUGGGAUUGUCGUCUAGGUAAGAGGAGAUAAUGAGUGAAAGUGACUGGGCCUCGGAAAUGCAGCCCCACCCACGGUGAAGUCUGCACCAGAGCACAGACUUGUCCUACUUCGGGCCAUAUGUAUAGGUAAUGCCCAUGUACUUUGUGUGUCGGUGGCUGCUGAUUUGGCCUGAUCAGUCCUUCUGCAGCCUUGGGGCAGUGUUUCAAGCUAGUUGGUGUCCUCUUUCCUCUGCUUGACCCCUGGAAUUCAGAGUCUAAUAGUAGACACCUCCCAUCCCCCACCCAAGGCCUGGUCCUUUCCUUUGCUUGAGCUUUUAUUCCUCAAGAAAAGAACUCCAAGGAAGGGUGAUGUGGUUUGUUAGGGUUCCCCAGUUUUCGUCCACUUCCAUCUUAUUCCUCGGAGAUCCCGCAAUUGCAAACCCCCUGGCAGCCUCCUGGCACCUGCAUUUGCCUUUAAAGCUUAGAAACAGCUGGGAAUGCACUCCUUGUACAGUCCAGUCCGUUUUCAGACAAAGUCGCUGCUAGUCUUCACACGCUUGAUGUCACUUUGUCUGAUUGGAAUAUGCGUGUCAUUGCUCUUGUUUCCGAGUUUGGCGUGAGAAAGGCAGGGUUCUCCAGGCAUGGUCAGGGAGCUUCCCCACCGUUUCCCAUUGGGCUCAGAUUCCAGCCAUUACCGAGACAAAUCCAAGCCUUCUCACGCAACGUGGAAGCGUGGUGACACCCUGGGGUGUGUGGAGGUGGCUGCUAGUGUUCCUAUUUACUGCCCUCCUUGCACACAGAAGGGAGAGGCCACUUAGGGGACCUUGUCUUCUCCGUAGUAUUUCUAGUCCUUGCCAAUCUUGAACUUGAGUGGACUUCUCAUAUUACAUUCAGCUCCCAGAAAUUCACUCCAGUCCUUCCUGGAGCAUUGUGAAAUUAGAAACCUGAACUCAUCAGCAAACCCCACCCACUCUUUGAAUCGGGACACCAGGAAACCCGUUACUACUAAUGUGAUCUUACCAUCUUAAUCCUUUCUUUCAAAAAUACGUGACUCUUUCACAGCCAUAUUUUAGCGUCAGGAAAAGCCAUGCUUAGAGGGAUUGGUCUUCAAAAUUUUGUGUGUGAUGCCCAAUGUGUAGGCCAUAUUGAAAGGUGAACGCACCAAAGGAUCGACCCUGUCACCUUGGAUGGUCUCUAUUUUGACCCUGUUGCCCAUGGAGAGGUAUUUUACCCUUUUGCUUCUUUGCUCAGGUGGUCCAGGGUUGUCUGUAGCCCAGGAAGCGGACUGACCCUGUAUCUUGAAAGAUAAGACCAGGAACCGGGAGUGAGGCUGGGACUCUCACUCAGCCUUUUCACGGUCAGUCUUGGUCUUCUCAUACUUAUUUCAAGAUGGCACCAGGACACACCUUCUUUUGUCCACCUGUUGACACCAUCACCCUCUUUCAUCAAGGUGAUCUCUUUCAUCAGGGCAUAUAUGAGACUUGGUGCUCCACCAGACUGUCUUCUCCCCUACCCCUGCCCCUUCCACAAAGCCAUUUCUCAAGUCGCAGUGGGAAAAGAUACCAAGACACCUGAUUUCUUGAACCAUUCUUGCUUCAGCAUGUGAAUUCUUUAAGACACUACUCACAUAUGCCAUUGGAGAGAAACAACCCGUUCUGCAUCACCAUAAUGAACCGAUCAGUCAUUCAUCCUCUUAUUCAACAAAUACUUGUUCCACUUCUACCACACUGGCCAUACAGUUGGAGGCAAGAUGGGCACAGUUAUGGCCUUGUGGGCUUUAUAUUCUACAGUGGGAGGAGGUGGAUGGUUAAUGUGAAAGCAAACCAAAAUAAUUUCCAGAGAGAGAAGAGGCAGGAAGAGAGCAGAGCAGAGUGAUGGGGCUGGGGGCAGAGAAGGAGAGAGGGGAAGAGGGAGAGAGUGGGGGGCAUUGAAGGGGAAGAAAGAGAGGCAGGGGUUGUCUACGUCUCCUCCUCCUGCGACCCAUCACCUACUGGAAAAUUACCACUUGCUGCUUGAGGGUUGGUCUGGUGUUGGAUGGAGGAAGAAGGCCUUAGUCUUAGCUCUUGGAUAAAAUGCAGUGCAGCACUGAAGAUAAGACAUCGCAGUUGUUACGACGCCUGGUUCUCCACCAAAUUCCUCUGUCAUUCCAGCAAGAGUGGAAGCAGAGGGGCAGGGGCAGGGGCAGGAUGAGGGCUGCUGCCCUGGUGAUGAGCUUGCCCCAUCCCUGGGCACUGGCUCUGCCCAGCCCCUCCCAUGUUGGUCCCAUCUGUCAGGUUGCCAGGCCAAGCAGGUCUCAGGUCAGCCAGGUCUCAAGGAGGAUAAGGGGGUUCAACGUCAGCGACUUGGCCCACGGGGCACGGGCACCUUGGGGAUGCCAUUCUUCUUGGUGCCAGAAGGCAGCUGCAUCUCCAGAAGCUCCCCCAGCACUGAGCUCACUUAGUGGCAUCCUUCUUAAACAGCAUCUGCUUUUAAGUAAGCAGCUAUUCCAAAACAUGCCGUGAUUCAUGUAAUUUUUGAGUGGUUACUUUGGUGCAGUUUGUCAAUUUGCUCUACCAUACUGUUUUUUGAUUAUUUGUUUGUUUUCUAGUGUAAAUAGCACAGCCCACAUAAAUGAGCGAAACUCAUCAUCUGAGGAUCUUUGAUUAUUCUUCCCCACUUAUUGUACAUUGAUGUGCCGCCUGCUAGGAAGAUAAACUCCCUCUUUGCUCACUCUGAGCCAGGAUCUCUGUGUUAGUUACACUCAGCCUUAUCUGAGCAUUCCAGGGAGGUCUUAAAUGAAUGUUUGGGGUUUUGAAACAUGCUACCAGCCCUUCCUUCCAAAGAGCAUGAAGCAUGGCUCUGUGUGGUUUUGUGUGUCUAGGUUUAGAGCUUGUAUUUGGAUGUAAGGAGUGACUAAAAACAGGUCUAGGCAGAGAACUGCUAUCUUUUAAACCACCCCAGCCCUCAGUCGAACAGAAAGAAUGAGCGUCUUCUGAUGUCAAAUCAUUCUAGAAAGGUCUUAGCUAGUGAGCACAAAGUAGCCAAUCCCGGGAGUUUAUAUGGGCCUCCAUGUGACCAAGCCAUCCCUAGCUAGGAAACUUAACUCUUUGCACAACCUCCCUUUAUGCUGAAGGGCCCUUGGGAACAUGGGAACAUUUGCACUUUGUCAGAGGAGUGGCCCCACCCUACUCUCUGCCUGAAACACAAAGCAGCUCCCCUCAGAACAGCCAGCCCGGUGCAGAAGCACUUGAACUUCUCAUCUUCCAUCUUAUUUCACUUUGGUUGCAGGGAGUUAAAUACAUAGGCCACAGCAGACUAAGGGAGCGGUGUGCACAAUGGCCCCCAGAAUAUCCAGUGACCCAAGUGAUGUUAGUCUUAGGGUCCCUAAGGCAGUAGGGCAUGGGGAGGAAAGUUCUCUCCAUCGAUUCCCAAACACACCAGCCACAAGUCCACACUCCACACCUGUAAACGCACAGCCCAUGCCCCAUUGUAAAGGUGACUGAAGAGAAUGGUCAACUCGGUGGUGAUGGGCCUGUUUUGGAGCUAAAAGCAUAAAAUGAAUCCUCCCUGUAGCUCCAUUGCCUUUUCCUCGUGAAGGAUUCCCUGCUAAAUGUUCUAAGAGUUACUGUACAUAGAAUCAAGAGAGCAGUUUUGAAUGAGCCGUAAAUCUGAGUCAUAUAUAAGAGGCAUAAUAUAAAUUGGGCCAAGCUUGCCCAUGUGGGACACACAGGUUUAUAGAGAUUAAACACUAGUGAGUAGCGGGGGAAGGGAACAGUGACUGUAUAAAUGGCCAUAUAAAUGACCUACUUGUCUUCUCAUGUAGGCUGGAAUCAGAACCUACGUAUGCUGUAGAUAACAGUCAAUUAAAUGGGUUAAUGUUCUAAGCCAAGAGAGUUCUAAGCCAAGACAUGUGCUUGGGACUGGAUUAACUCUUGUCAAUAUCUUGGAUUCCAUAGUAAAACAUCUGUUAAGUAACAUGCGGCAGGAAAGGAUGCAGGGAGCAUUGGACUGUAGGAAAUUCUCCUUUAUACAAGUUAAUUAGUUUUGUCUCUGGUGGCUGUCUCUUAAAACAGAAUCCCCUGGAGACCCGGGUUUUCAUUUUGUAAUUCAACACCCAAAUAUUUGCAACACUAAAUAACAACUCCCUAAAGACUUCAGUCUUGCAUGGGCAUAAGCAACUCACACUGGUUAGCUUUUGUCAGAUUUCGUCGUUUCCGCAGCAAAAUUUCUUAGUGUUGAUGUUGAUAGCUUCUGGGUUGGCAAACUGGCAGUUCACUCUAGUCUUACUGGGUUGGGCAAGUCCUUGCCCCUAGAAAAUUGGGGAUAGCUUUGGCCAUGGGAGGAGCAAGAACACUACGCAGUCGUAAGCUCUGUUUUUUGUUUUGUUUUGUUUUGUUUUGUUUUCGGCACCAUUAUGUACGAUGAAGACUUACAGCCACUGCUAAUACAGCAUAGGGGACACUUUGAGGAGCCCUAGUAUCAUUGUUUGAAAUCAUUGUACAGGGAACUGCAGGGGUGAACACCAUUGUACCAAUCCCCGGGCCAGUGUCUCAUUUCCUAACAGAAUCAUCCCAUUCUUGUUCACUCUUCAGUCAUCCCAAGCCAAAAGGGAAAAUUCGAAACCCACUGUGACACCCCAACCCUAAUUUCCAACCUUUGGAGGACUCACCUGGGGCAGAAGGGAGAAAGGGCUUUGCUGAAGUCUCAGGCUGCCGAGAGCCAUGUAUGGGCAUAGGAGCAAGCUGAUGGCAUGGCUCUUGACAAGGUUUUCUAUAGGGCAGCAGCUGCUGCUCCCAGGGGAACCCUCUCCUGUUGCCUCCGCAGUCUAUUCUGGGGUGGAAACACCAUUCUCUAUUAUUUCUCUCACAUACAUGUGGAUUUCUAAUAUCAAGUUAUGUGACUGCCUACCACUUAAGGCCUACAAAACCACAUGGGAGUUUCUUUAUUGCGUAUGCAGCCAGUCAACAUGAAUGGGACCCUAGAAACUGUGAGGAGCAGGAUUCUCUAAGGUGCUCUUAGAUACGGUGUCACUUCCACAUACAAGCACAAUUCUCCCAGUUAAGGGGCUGGAAGACAAGCGGGGCAACUGGUUUUGAAAAGCCCGCUGGCGUGCCAGAGGGGGUGUUUGCCCACACCCUCCUUGAAUUUAACUGCCACAAUCUAUCCGCAGAUGUGUUUUGUUCUAUUUCUUGUUUUUCACUAGCGUUUGCGUUGCUUCCUCUGAAGCCAGAGGGUGAAAGGCCCUAGCAAAGUUAGUUAUCAGUCAACUGAUGAUAACUGUGAUCCUUAAAGAUGAAUUCCCAGCCUGAGGUGACACACAGAGGUUCAGCAGACGUCUCAGGAUCUGUCAUAUGUCAUGUUGCUUGGUGUGAAGAUGGAAGAACAAAGUCCACAUCAGUUUCUGCUCCUUCAAACAGUGUGUCGAUAUGAAACAUUGAGAUUUGGCAGAAACAUGUGCCUAGUUUGCAGCACCAAAUACUGGUCUUCUCAGAAGUGUUUCUGUUUUUUUGUUUUUGUUUUUGUUUUUGUUUUUGUUUUUGUUUUGUUUAAUUUCCUCUUCUGGCAUCCCAAUUUGGAUCAUUUCCUCUCUUUCUUUCCUGGAGAAACAGGAUGGCAGGUGCUGGAGCCCAGAGAGGGGGUCACCCUCCAGCUAAAAUGAUUUAAAUGGAAAGGAGAAUGACAGCAAAGCCUCACGUGAACUUUAAUGACCUUAUCAAUGACCUUUACUAACUGACUCUUGGUACCCGGAUUGUUGAGAGGUGAGUGGGACUAAAAGCCAGGAUCAAGAUCAGGUUGCUCCACACAUUUGCAGAUCAGGAACCCCGGGAAUAUGAGUUAGACCCAGAAAGUAUUGAACUGGACAUUGAAUGAAGCUUGAGGCCAUGCAUUGAUAACAUUUUUAGAGUCUGUUACAUUAUUUUCUCAAAAGGAACACAUGUUUACUACAAACCAUUUAGAAAAUACCAAUAACCAAACAGAAGGGAAAUGUCUGGAACCUUCCAGUUGUUUAAUUCUGUAGAAACUGUUCACGAAAGGCUGAAUGAGUGGGGACAAGUCACAGAGAUCUCGCCAUGGUUAGCACCAGGGACAAGUCUGGCUCUAAUGUAUGUUUUAUGAAGUCUGAUUAGCUUUGAAAUGCAUCUUUGCCAGCUGAACUUGUCAUGCACUAAACUUCCCAUUGAUCAUUAGAGUGUCUACGAUUAAGUGGAAAAGGUGGUCAACCAUUUGGAUGUUUGACUUUCACAACAUCAAGCAUUGGCCAUUGGGCGUAUCUGGGCAUUGGUAUGGAAUAAACAGGAUACUCAGUGAAACAUCCAAACUAUUGACUGGAUUUUUCCCAUGGGGCAUCUGUCUAAGAGUCACAGAUCUGAGAAAUAGAAGGACCAGGUCCGUGUGGAUGCUCCUAGUGCGUUCAAAUAACCCUUGAAUUCACCAGGUCUCAUUGCAUUUAUUUAAAGAUGGAGCCCAUUGUCCCCCCUCCUCCUCAGCUCACCCAUGGAACUAGAAAUUCACAAACCUGAAGCUGAACCACAGGACAAGAAAUUAAACAGCAACGGCCACAUGGCCUCUUUUUUCACAGGUUUUGCAUUGAAUGUUUUAGAACUUUAUUCCCCCGCCCCCUCACCCAUGUAUACCAAAACUGGUUUUAUUUUCAUUUUCCUAAAUUAUUUUCUGAUACAAUAAACUGUUAACUGUUUAUUUAUACUUUUACAAGGAGCACUUGUUAUUUUUCAAAAGGAAAACAAAAGCCUCUCUGUUUUCAUGUUCUCCGUAUAUCUAUACCACAGCUGUCUCUAUAGACGUAUUUAUAUAUCAUCUUCUUGAGAGAGUUAACCUCCUGUAGUUUAAUGUUGUGUUUCUUUUCUUUAAAUGCAUAUCAUAAUCAUGUUAAUAAACAAAAAUGACACAAUAUAUGUGGGUGGGGGGCGGGGGGCAGGUGGCUGGGUGUGAUUUCCGUACAGGUGAACUUUUAUUCCAGAUUUUUUUAAGUUGUUUCUGUAUUUCAAAGCUAUGUAUUUGGAAAACAUUGUAAAUGAAACACCUAUAUUAACUUUCCUGUGUAUAUUUAGUACUCUGAUGUUGCUAUUAAAAAAAAAAACAUAAUAUGAAAAAAAAAAAAAA